GCGAAGGAGCUCCCAGCCAUGGAAAGCCCUGGAGAGUCAGGCGCGGGCUCUCCUGGAGCCCCCAGCCCGUCCAGCUUCACUACUGGGCACCUGGCGAGAGAAAAGUUAGUGAAGUUGGCAGGGCAGCCAGGCCAGCCCAGGACCCACUGUAUGACGUGCCCAAUGCCAGCGGCGGGCAGGCAGGCGGGCCGCAGCGGCCGGGGCGCGUUGUGAGCCUGCGGGAGCGCCUGCUGCUCACCCGGCCCGUGUGGCUGCAGCUGCAAGCCAACGCAGCGGCCGCACUGCACAUGCUGAGGACCGAGCCCCCGGGGACGUUCCUCGUGCGGAAAUCUAACACCCGCCAGUGCCAGGCCCUGUGCAUGCGGUUGCCUGAAGCCAGUGGCCCCUCCUUCGUCUCCAGCCACUACAUCCUGGAGAGCCCUGGCGGCGUCUCCUUGGAGGGCUCGGAGCUCAUGUUCCCAGACCUAGUCCAGCUCAUCUGUGCCUACUGCCACACCCGGGACAUCCUUCUCCUCCCGCUGCAGCUCCCCAGAGCCAUCCACCACGCAGCCACUCACAAAGAGCUGGAGGCCAUCUCCCAUCUGGGCAUUGAGUUCUGGAGCUCCUCCCUCAACAUCAAGGCUCAGCGGGGCCCGGCUGGAGGCCCAGUGUUGCCCCAGCUGAAGGCCCGGUCCCCUCAAGAGCUGGACCAGGGCACCGGAGCCGCCUUGUGCUUCUUCAACCCCCUGUUCCCGGGGGACCUAGGGCCCACCAAGCGGGAGAAAUUCAAGAGAAGCUUCAAAGUGCGCGUGUCCACAGAGACCUCCAGCCCCCUGUCUCCACCUGCCGUGCCACCUCCCCCCGUCCCCGUGCUGCCAGGGGCAGUCCCCAGCCAGACAGAGCGGCUGCCCCCUUGCCAGCUGCUACGGAGGGAGAGCUCAGUGGGGUACCGCGUGCCAGCAGGCAGUGGCCCUAGCCUUCCGCCUAUGCCCUCCCUCCAAGAGGUGGACUGCGGCUCCCCCAGCAGCUCCGAGGAGGAGGGGGUGCCAGGGUCCCGGGGGAGCCCAGCGACCUCACCCCACCUGGGCCGCCGACGACCUCUGCUUCGGUCCAUGAGCGCCGCCUUCUGCUCCCUACUGGCACCGGAGCGGCAGGUGGGCCGGGCUGCGGCAGCACUGAUGCAGGACCGACACACAGCCGCGGGCCAGCUGGUGCAGGACCUACUGACCCAGGUGCGGGCUGGGCCCGAGCCCCAGGAGCUGCAGGGCAUCCGUCAGGCGCUGAGCCGGGCCCGGGCCAUGCUGAGUGCGGAGCUGGGCCCUGAGAAGCUGCUGUCGCCUAAGAGGCUGGAACAUGUCCUGGAGAAGUCAUUGCAUUGCUCUGUGCUCAAGCCUCUCCGGCCCAUCCUGGCAGCCCGCCUGCGGCGCCGGCUUGCCGCAGACGGCUCCCUGGGCCGCCUAGCUGAGGGCCUCCGCCUGGCCCGGGCCCAGGGCCCCGGAGCCUUCGGGUCCCACCUGAGCCUGCCCUCCCCAGUAGAGUUGGAGCAAGUGCGCCAGAAGCUGCUGCAGCUGCUCCGCACCUACUCACCCAGCGCCCAGGUCAAGCGGCUCCUGCAGGCCUGCAAGCUGCUCUACAUGGCCCUGAGGACCCAGGAAGGGGAGGGCGCGGGUGCCGACGAGUUCCUGCCUCUGCUGAGCCUCGUCUUGGCCCACUGUGACCUUCCUGAGCUGCUGCUGGAGGCCGAGUACAUGUCGGAGCUGCUGGAGCCCAGCCUGCUUACUGGAGAGGGUGGCUACUACCUGACCAGCCUCUCUGCCAGCCUGGCCCUGCUGAGUGGCCUGGGUCAGGCCCACACCCUCCCACUGAGCCCCGUGCAGGAGCUACGGCGCUCCCUCAGCCUCUGGGAGCAGCGCCGCCUGCCUGCCACCCACUGCUUCCAGCACCUCCUCCGAGUAGCCUAUCAGGAUCCCAGCAGUGGCUGCACCUCCAAGACCCUGGCCGUGCCCCCAGAAGCCUCGAUUGCCACCCUGAACCAGCUCUGUGCCACCAAGUUCCGAGUGACCCAGCCCAACACUUUUGGCCUCUUCCUGUACAAGGAGCAGGGCUACCACCGCCUGCCCCCUGGGGCCCUGGCCCACAGGCUGCCCACCACUGGCUACCUCGUCUACCGCCGGGCGGAGUGGCCUGAGACCCAGGGGGCUGUGACAGAGGAGGAGGGCAGUGGGCAGUCAGAGGCAAGAAGCAGAGGGGAGGAGCAAGGGUGCCAGGGAGAUGGGGAUGCUGGGGUCAAAGCCAGCCCCAGGGACAUUCGGGAACAGUCUGAGACAACUGCUGAAGGGGGCCAGGGUCAAGCCCAGGAAGGCCCUGCUCAGCCAGGGGAACCAGAGGCAGAGGGAAGCCGGGCAGCAGAGGAGUAGCUUGAAGUGGCCAGAAGGGUCAUUCGGGGCGGGAGACCCUGAGCCUGCUGAGAAAUCCUUUUAGCGCCAGCAAGCCCCACCCAGGGCCCUGUCCUGUGUCUGCCACCACCUUUGUCUGAUACUUGUUUCCAGGGAAGCUGGGGGAACUGCCACAUCUGAGGAACUGGAAUAAAGAUGAGGGGGCUUCGGGGGCCCCCAGACUGUGUGCCCAAGGCCCCUUGCCUCUUGUUCUUCUCCCCCAGCUGAGGGUGAGCCAGCCUGCAAUGAGGGUGUGCCAAGUGGGGGCGAAUCCGACAGAUGCCCAACCUCUGACGUGGGGAGGGUGACGGUCUCAGCUCCUUUUACCCUUCCCCUCAUGGGCAUGGCUGAGGCAGGGCUCCACCCAAGUAUCUCCCACCAGGCUGGGACUUCCAGACCCUAAAAGGUUCCAAUGGCUCUUAGGUGUCAGGAGGAUUUAGAGAGGCCACAGAACAGCAGCAAAGGCUUGGGGCCCACCCCUGUCCUGGACACCAGAAGGACCUGCACCUGCAAGCCUCAGUACUCUCAUCUGUAAAGUGGGGACACUAUUGCUGCCCUGCUCGGCUCCCAGAAGUGUCCCAGUGAUCAAAAUGGGUGAUUUUGCUACAAGCAGAGCUCAUGGCAGAAAGGGAGGGAGAGAGCUGGGCUGCUAACUCUCUCCCGGAGUCCGCUCUCUGCCAGACAGGGCUCCCACCUGCUGAUGCCCAGUUCAGGGAGGUUAUUCCCCUGGAAAUCAGGCCCUGGGGAGAAAGUACCCAAGUUACAGUCUCUCCCCAAGAUUUGGAGUCCUCCCAGGCCCUCCAGCAUCUCUGGGGAGAUCCACCAGCUGGCAGAUAAGCUUCCAGAAUGGAGAGGGGGCUCAGAAACCAUGCUCUCUGCACUAAACUCUUGGCCCUCACAAAAGCUUUACUUGGCCAUGACUUGUUGGGCCCACUGAGGGUCAGGAAAGUGACUCCCAGGAUGUCAUAUAGCAAGUCCUUAAGGGUUCCCCCGCCCAAACCAGGGCAUCAGGUUCCAACUCCACCCUCCAUUCUAAGCCACCCACAAAGGCCGGGGCAGCCCCCAAGGAAGCCCAGAGCAGGCAGCAAAUCCAAACAAGGAAAAGUGCCGACCACCAACCACGAGGGGGUGUGCACGGCCCGGGAAUCUGCCGAGAGGGUGACCACCCAGGGGUGAGGGCGCCUCCAAGGCUGCAGCAGCAGAGGGGGUCCCGGGCCUUGCAGUCCAGCAGCAUCAGGCAACCUGGGGACAGCGCAGGGGCCAAGGCCACUGGCCCCCAGGUCCCUUAGAUUCUGGGGUCUGGGUAAGGCCAGCCUCUUGGGGGCCAUCCCCAGGAAGGAAGGAAUUGUCCCCUUAUGGAGGAUGACCCCAGAGGCUCUCUCCUCGGGCACUGAGCACAGAGGGGACGUCAGCCCAAAUGUCAGACAUGACAACUGGGAGGUAGAAAUCGUGGACAUUGGCUUUUUGGGUUUUUUUGUUUGUUUGUUUGUUUGAGAUGGAGUUUUGCUCUGUCGCUCUGGCUAAAGUGCAGUGGUGCCAUCUCGGCUCACAGCAACCUUCGCCUCCCAGUUCAAGUGAUUCUCCUGCCUCAGCCUCCCGAGUAGCUGGGACUACAGGUGUGCACCACCACACCUGGCUAAUUUUUGUGUUACUAGUAGAGACGGGGUUUCCCCAUGUUGGCCAGGCUGGUCUCAAACUCCCGACCUCAGGUGAUCCGCCCGCCUUGGCCUCCCAAAGUACUGGGAUUACAGGCGUGAGCUACCACACCCAGCCAGACAUUGACUUUCAGAUGAGCAGUCCAGAUACAGCCCAGUUGCACGGCUCCCAUUUUUUUUGUCACUAGGCCACCAGCAGCUCUUCCCUCCCCACUUCCACGCCCUCCCAAGGUUCUCGCUGAUAGGAAGUGUCCCGUUGGCUCUUCUAUUCCCCUCCCUGUUUCACCACUCACCCCUAGUGCCUCACACAGUCCAAUGCUGAGCACAAAUGCCAUAGGUGUUCAAUAAAUGUUGUUCACUGA